GAGGCGGAGCGGAAGCCGAGUGCGAGGGACGAGCGGAGUAAAAUCUCCACAAGCUGGGAACAAACCUCGUCCCAACUCCCACCCACCGGCGUUUCUCCAGCUCGAUCUGGAGGCUGCUUCGCCAGUGUGGGACGCAGCUGACGCCCGCUUAUUAGCUCUCGCUGCGUCGCCCCGGCUCAGAAGCUCCGUGGCGGCGGCGACCGUGACGAGAAGCCCACGGCCAGCUCAGUUCUCUUCUACUUUGGGAGAGAGAGAAAGUCAGAUGCCCCUUUUAAACUCCCUCUUCAAAACUCAUCUCCUGGGUGACUGACUACUUGGAAGAUGAACUGUUCUCAUCAGCAACAUGCUAUUAUGUCAUCUUUUAGGACUAGGUAAUGCUCCAGUGACUUAAUACCAAUGACAUUUUCAUGUUGUCCACAAAUUCUGAGUAGAAACCUUUUCAAGCCUGUAGCCUCUCUGAGAGCUGACUGUUAUUAACUGAAUGAGAGGAUGUCAGCAAACAGAGUUAAUAGAGUGGAUACAACCUUGCUGAAGAUGAAGAAUAUACAAUAUUGAGGAUAUUUUUUUCUUUUUUUUUUCAAGUCUUGAUUUGUGGCUUACCUCAAGUUACCAUUUUUCAGUCAAGUCUGUUUGUUUGCUUCUUCAGAAAUGUUUUUUACAAUCUCAAGAAAAAAUAUGUCCCAGAAAUUGAGUUUACUGUUGCUUGUAUUUGGACUCAUUUGGGGAUUGAUGUUACUGCACUAUACUUUUCAACAACCAAGACAUCAAAGCAGUGUCAAGUUACGUGAGCAAAUACUAGACUUAAGCAAAAGAUAUGUUAAAGCUCUAGCAGAGGAAAAUAAGAACACAGUGGAUGUCGAGAACGGUGCUUCUAUGGCAGGAUAUGCGGAUCUGAAAAGAACAAUUGCUGUCCUUCUGGAUGACAUUUUGCAACGAUUGGUGAAGCUGGAGAACAAAGUUGACUAUAUUGUUGUGAAUGGCUCAGCAGCCAACACCACCAAUGGUACUAGUGGGAAUUUGGUGCCAGUAACCACAAAUAAAAGAACGAAUGUCUCGGGCAGUAUCAGAUAGCAGUUGAAAAUCACCUUGUGCUGCUCCAUCCACUGUGGAUUAUAUCCUAUGGCAGAAAAGCUUUAUAAUUGCUGGCUUAGGACAGAGCAAUACUUUACAAUAAAAGCUCUACACAUUUUCAAGGAGUAUGCUGGAUUCAUGGAACUCUAAUUCUGUACAUAAAAAUUUUAAAGUUAUUUGUUUGCUUUCAGGCAAGUCUGUUCAAUGCUGUACUAUGUCCUUAAAGAGAAUUUGGUAAUUUGGUUGAUGUGGUAAGCAGAUAGGUGAGUUUUGUAUAAAUCUUUUGUGUUUGAGAUCAAGCUGAAAUGAAAACACUGAAAAACAUGGAUUCAUUUCUAUAACACAUUUAUUUAAGUAUAUAACACGUUUUUUGGACAAGUGAAGAAUGUUUAAUCAUUCUGUCAUUUGUUCUCAAUAGAUGUAACUGUUAGACUACGGCUAUUUGAAAAAAUGUGCUUAUUGUACUAUAUUUUGUUAUUCCAAUUAUGAGCAGAGAAAGGAAAUAUAAUGUUGAAAAUAAUGUUUUGAAAUCAUGACCCAAAGAAUGUAUUGAUUUGCACUAUCCUUCAGAAUAACUGAAGGUUAAUUAUUGUAUAUUUUUAAAAAUUACACUUAUAAGAGUAUAAUCUUGAAAUGGGUAGCAGCCACUGUCCAUUACCUAUCGUAAACAUUGGGGCAAUUUAAUAACAGCAUUAAAAUAGUUGUAAACUCUAAUCUUAUACUUAUUGAAGAAUAAAAGAUAUUUUUAUGAUGAGAGUAACAAUAAAGUAUUCAUGAUUUUUCACAUACAUGAAUGUUCAUUUAAAAGUUUAAUCCUUUGAGUGUCUAUGCUAUCAGGAAAGCACAUUAUUUCCAUAUUUGGGUUAAUUUUGCUUUUAUUAUAUUGGUCUAGGAGGAAGGGACUUUGGAGAAUGGAACUCUUGAGGACUUUAGCCAGGUGUAUAUAAUAAAGGUACUUUUGUGCUGCAUUAAAUUGCUUGGAAAAUGUUAACAUUAUAUUAUAUAAGAGUAUCCUUUAUGAAAUUUUGAAUUUGUAUAACAGAUGCAUUAGAUAUUCAUUUUAUAUAAUGGCCACUUAAAAUAAGAACAUUUAAAAUAUAAACUAUGAAGAUUGACUAUCUUUUCAGGAAAAAAGCUGUAUAUAGCACAGGGAACCCUAAUCUUGGGUAAUUCUAGUAUAAAACAAAUUAUACUUUUAUUUAAAUUUCCCUUGUAGCAAAUCUAAUUGCCACAUGGUGCCCUAUAUUUCAUAGUAUUUAUUCUCUAUAGUAACUGCUUAAGUGCAGCUAGCUUCUAGAUUUAGACUAUAUAGAAUUUAGAUAUUGUAUUGUUCGUCAUUAUAAUAUGCUACCACAUGUAGCAAUAAUUACAAUAUUUUAUUAAAAUAAAUAUGUGAAAUAUUGUUUCAUGAAAGACAGAUUUCCAAAUCUCUCUUCUCUUCUCUGUACUGUCUACCUUUAUGUGAAGAAAUUAAUUAUAUGCCAUUGCCAGGUAGAAGUUUGGAAUAAUUGUUUAGUCUCUCCUAUUAGAUGUGGACAUUUUUGUUUUUGUUUUUGUUUUCAGGGAUGAAAUAAAAUAUAUUAUUUCUACCUA